AGUUAGAGAACUAACUGCCAAGAUGGAGCGAAGGGAACAUUUAACCUUGACUUUCCACAGUCCUGAGGUUCCCAAAAUAAAGGGGAACCGGAAAUACCAAAGGGUGAGGAGCCUACCGUCCCUGCCAAGAAACAUCCAAGUGCCUCGAUGUCAUGCCAAAGGCAGCAGCAGCUUAUGGAUCAGGCACACAUCUACAUCCGAACGCUCUGUGGCAGCCUCUGUAGUUUUAGCCUCCUAAUGCUGAUCGCCAUGUCCCCACUGAACUGGGUACAGUUUCUGGUGAUCAAGAAUGGCCUUGAGCUCUACGCAGGACUCUGGACCUUAUGCAACCAUGAGCUGUGCUGGAGCCACACACCCAAGCCACCCUAUUAUCUCCAAUAUUCCAGGGCCUUCUUUCUCAUCUCUGUCUUUACCAUACUUACUGGCCUUGGCUGGCUCUUCAGCUCUUGGAUCCUUAAUCGAGGAAGCAUGACCACCAACUUGGAUCUGAAGGUAUCCAUGCUCAGCUUCAUCUCAGCUACCUGCUUGCUCCUCUGCCUCAACCUGUUUGUGGCACAGGUUCACUGGCAUACUAGGGAUGCCAUGGAGUCAGAUCUCCUAUGGACCUAUUAUCUUAACUGGUGCAGUGACAUCUUUUACAUGUUUGCUGGGAUCAUCUCUCUUCUCAACUACUUAACUUCCAGAUCGCCUGCCUGUGAUGAAAACGUCACUGUGAUUCCAACAGAGAGAUCAAGGCUGGGGGUUGGUCCGGUGACUACAGUAUCACCUGCUAAAGAUGAAGGGCCAAGGUCUGAGAUGGAAUCUCUAAGUGUGAGAGAGAAAAAUUUACCAAAGUCAGGACUGUGGUGGUGAUAGGAAAACCUAACUAUAGCUUGUCUUAAAAGCAGGGGAGAAGCUGAGUUGGGAAUGGUCACAUAAAUUCUGGGAAACUCUCCUAAUAUCAUGUCCAUAUUACUUGAGGAGACAGCAUUAAAGCUGAUGAAAUGUCUUUUGCGUGCAUUGGAUCCAAAAUAUAUAUGAUAGUCAUAAAGUAAAUAACUCACUUAAGAAAAACAUUUCUAAAAGAAAACAACAAUGUUUAGAGUCAUGAAUGAAAGAAACUAGUGAAAGAUGCAGUGUGUAGACCAGAGACCUCUUUGGGUAUCAGGGAUCUCAUGGACCAGAAUGGCCCGUGGAGAAGAAUGUUAAUUACUUCUGUUUGGAAUUUUCUUUAUUAUGUGUGGCUUUGGGUAUACUCAGGAUGGAAAGCACUUGGACAAAUACUGUUGAAUCUGAACUUAAUAGCAUUACCAGAAAUGGAAUAAAUAUCAAUGGAUAUAAGACCUA